GCCCCAGGGCUGGGGCCAGCGUGCUGGAUUUCCUUCCCACUCCCGUUUCCCUCCUGGCAGUUCAUUUUUGGGGAGCAGGAGAGCUGUGACUGGGGAAGGACAGCCUGCGUCUCCCCCAGCAGCCACCCACUGCCCCUGGCACAGUGGUGGGACCUGACUCCCUACCUCCUGGGGCCCUCCAGGGUCCCCCAGCCCCAGGCUUUCCUGUUGCCCACAGCAGCACAGGCCUUUGGUUUACCCGCCACCGCUCGAGGGCCUGGCUUCCUGCCACCAUGCCUUGCUUGUCACCAGCCUCCUAAAAUAGCCAUCGAAGUGGUGCGUCUGCUCCUGUGUACUUCUGGGACAUCUGGCAAAUAAGGCAGGUUUUGCCCCUGCCCAGCCAGACCCUGAGCUGUGACACGCAGGCCUCUGAGGCCAGGGUACCAAAGAAAGGGCCCGUCUCUCUGGGGCUGGCCACAGGGGCCAGUUGUCCCUCCUGCGCCAUACAUCUGUGCCUGCUGGCUGGAGGGACAAGCUGUGGCGCCCGAGCCCAGCCGUUCCCCUUCCCUGGCAUUUUCCCAAAGGAAGGGCCCAUUCGUGCGGAACCCCAGCAGCCAGAAAACCUGAGUAGCUGACGUCCUGGGCGGUGGGUGCUGCAGGAGUCGGAGCUGCCCUGAUGGAUUGGCGGGGGCAGCAGCACAGGUGGGGUGGAUAUGCCAGCACCCCCCUAGACUGAUGUGAGCUUAGGGGUCCCACCUCAGAAAUGAGGGGUGGCCAAUGCCCAGACUCUCUGGACUCAGAGGUGGCCCCACUGACUAUCCUAGUCAGUGUGGCUCCAAGUCCCCUCCUUGCUCUGGCAAACGGAUGCAGGUAAGUGUGUGUACAAGUUUGCCCGUGUGUGUGUGUGUGUGCGCAUGUGGCUGCGGUGAAGAGGGGCGAGGAAAGUCCUUUCUUUGAACUCCUUGGUGGGGACAUGGUGGCCUGUGGCUGGCCUUGUUUUUGGGUGCAAGGGCAUCUUCCAGGACCCUGACCCCUACUGGAUGCCUGUGCCCUGAGGCCCUGGCCAGGGCAGAUUUGGAGGAUCUGUUGAGGUUGGGGCAGAACUUGUGCUGCGUGUGUGAAUGGCUCACACAUUUGUCCGAUCAUCUAAUGAUCACUGCGGUCUCCGCGCAGGGUCCAACCCUGGACCACCUGCCCUCAGGGGCCAGAUUCUAGCCAGCUGGUAAAGCAAGUCCUUCUCAGAUGGCAUGCUGUCUGGGAAGGAGGGCUGGGGCCUCACCAAGAAGGGCCCUUGCAGGCUGUAUAGGAGUUUGCUCAGCUGCUGAGAGGAAGGCCGUGGCGGUCCGGCACAGGCCUGGAGGCCUUACAGACGAGCUCAGUAGGAAGCCCCAACUUCCUCCUGUCUCUCCCCUGAGGGGAGGGGGCUGGCUGAGCCCCCAGGAGGCAAUGGUGACAGUUGGAACAGCCAGCUUCAGGUGCUUCCGUCCCCAGGAGACAAGACCUGCCGAUUCCUUCCAGGGGAAUCACAGGCCAAGUUUCCAGGUGGGGACUCAUGGCAGGGAAGCUGACGGUACAGCCAGAGUCCCAGGCCUUGGUAGUGGCCCAGGAAGGUGGGAAGGUGGCAAAGCAGCCUGAGGGGCACCUCCGGGGCUUUGCAAGGCUCUGGGAUCCCAGCCCAAAGCCCCCUCCAAGCCCAGCAUGCCCCACACUCUAGAAAGUGGGGAGGGGCCAACAGGAGGGGGGUCGGUUUCUGAGGGCCUGCUGAAUGCCAGGCCCACCCUUGCCCACGCUGGGGAGGCAGCAUUGCCAUCCCCAUGACACAGCACAGGUGCCCAGGUCUCGGAGAGCCCCUCCCAGGGACAUGCACACCAGGCUUGCCCUUUGGAGCCUCUCCUGACCUUGGCCAGCGUGGGAGCUGCUGUUCCUGGGAGGAUCCGCCACCUGCCCCAGGCGCUCACCAGCCUGGCUUCCACAGCUGCUACCCACAGGGGCUGCCGGGGCCUGCAUGGCGUGGCAAGGGUCAGGGAUGGAUUCAGUGCCCGGCCAUCCUGGCUGCCCUGGCCACCCUCCUGGGAGCUGUCCUCAGCUUCACCUGCAUCCCCGCCAGCACCAAAGGGGCCAAAACUGACGCCCAGGCUCCACUGCCAGGCGGCCCCCGGGCCAGUGUGUUCGACCUGAAGGCCAUCGCCUCCCUGCUGCGGCUGCCAGACGUCCCGAGGAUCUUCCUGGUGAAGGUGGCCUCCAACUGCCCCACAGGGCUCUUCAUGGUCAUGUUCUCCAUCAUCUCCAUGGACUUCUUCCAGCUGGAGGCCGCCCAAGCUGGCUACCUCAUGUCCUUCUUCGGGCUCCUCCAGAUGGUGACCCAGGGCCUGGUCAUCGGGCAGCUGAGCAGCCACUUCUCGGAGGAGGUGCUGCUCCGGGCCAGCGUGCUGGUCUUCAUCGUGGUGGGCCUGGCCAUGGCCUGGAUGUCCAGCGUCUUCCACUUCUGCCUCCUGGUGCCCGGCCUGGUGUUCAGCCUCUGCACCCUCAACGUGGUCACCGACAGCAUGCUGAUCAAGGCUGUCUCCACCUCGGACACAGGGACCAUGCUGGGCCUCUGCGCCUCUGUACAACCACUGCUCCGAACUCUGGGACCCACGGUCGGCGGCCUCCUGUACCGCAGCUUUGGCGUCCCCGUCUUCGGCCACGUGCAGGUUGCUAUCAAUACCCUUGUCCUCCUGGUCCUCUGGAGGAAACCUAUGCCCCAGAGGAAGGACAAAGUCCGGUGACCGCUGCCCAGACACAGACUGGCAAUAAACUCCUACUAAAUCCCUCCGA